GCCACCGCACCCAGCCCCAGUGACCUUGUUUUAAGGACAUGACAUGGAAUUCCUGGAACCGGGAUCCGUUUUGAAGAGUCAGUGGUCCUAAGUUGUCAUCAGGCAGGGGACCAGGUUCUGCUCUGUGCGUUGGCCUCUGCUCCAGCCUGUGCAGGCUGUGUGGACGAGUGCCACCUGCAUCAGCGGGCACCUCGCAAGGCUUUGUUGAGCUCCAGUGAGUAGCCCACUUCCAUCUGCCCAUCUGGCUUGGACUUUCUGUACUUAUCUUAGUCCCAUGGCUGUGCUCCUGCAGGGCCAGGCAGAUGAUGGCAGCCGACAAUGUGCAUCUCAAAGGGACGACCACCCGAGGAAGGAUCCACAGGAAAUGUCGCAGGGGGUGGGUCGUGCCACAGCCCCUGGAAACGAGCCAGGAUGUUGCCCUUGAUCUUGCCUGCAUUCUGGCUUUGCACAUUGAGGGAGCUGCUUCGGCCCUUCCCUUGGUCUCUGGCUGUUUGAGCUUUAUAUAGAGAGCCGAGUAGGAGUCAACUCUUUGGGGCUGUCUCUUGUGAAGUCCUUCUUACCACGCGCCAUGCCUUUCUGGGCAGUGCGGCUGCAUCUUUCACACAUGGCUAUUCUCUUAGCAGUUUCUUACCCUGUACAGUUUAAAAACAAACAUCUUACCUAACCUGGAGUGCUUUCUACAUGCCCAUGACACCUUUCUCCUUACAGAGGAUGAAGAACCACGGAAAAACUUGGGGCUCCGAUAUUGCGAACUCCCUAAAUUCUCCCACCUCCUUUCCCACAUAACCUGAUGCUCAGCCUACUGCUGACAAGCGUCAGCCCAGCGGAGGCCCGUCUGCUCUGCCUUCGUCAUUUCUAGUCCCCUUCGGUUAUGUUUCAUGUUCCUCAUUCUCACAAGAAAGAAUCCCUUCCCUUCUACAGAUGGACGGCCCGUCUGUAGGCUGGUGCCAUCCUUCGAGGUCAGCUGGUGAUACACACUGAGAGGGAACCUAGGUCCAGAAUGUGCUUGUCAGGAAGGGUGUGCAGCCCAGGGUUCUCUCCGUGUUCACUGCCUCUUUCCUUUGUCAUCUUCAUUCUGCCGUUGAGCCUAUCUAGUGGGUUUUUACAAUUUCAGUUACUGUAUGUUUAGUUCGAAGUUUUCCAUUUGGUUCUCCUUUAUACCUUCUGUUUCUUUCCUGAGACUUCUCAUCAUUCCCUUUAUGUUAAGAAUACCCCUCCUUACUUCUUGGAGUGUUUUUUGUAAUAGCUGCUGUGGAGUCUGUCAGCUAAUUCCAAUGUCUCUGUUAGCUCAGAUAAGAUGUUGAUCAUCUUUUCCCAUGCGAGUUGAGGAUAUUCACCUUCUUUGUAUGCUGAGUGGUUCUGGAUUGGUCCUGAACAUUCUGAAUAUUACGUUAGGAAGCUGUGGUUCCUGAUUCAGUCCUCUGGAGAGUUGUUGGUAGCUUGGUUGUGGCAGGCACUCCACCAGCUUGGGUUCAGGUUCUCAGUCCCUACCAUUCUGCUGUGGGUUUUGGUGCCGUUUUCCAAGCCUUUGUCCACUCUUCAGAUCUGUCCACUAUGUAGCACUCCAUGGCCUGUGUGGGCCCCGGGCAUGCUCCGUCCUAACCUUCAGUGCUCAGGGUCUGUGCUUGAGGGCUCUGUUUACAUAUGCCUCGCUCAGGGCUGAGCCCAGGAGCUCGUAACAACUUGAUGGGGUUGUUUUCCCGAGAGCUCCUCCCUCUCUGCAAUCUCUCGAGCACUUUCCGGUUUCCUGGGCCUCCUAUCUUCACCCCUUCAGCCAGGAGGCAGGGCUUCAGUUAUCAGCUCUGCCACGCUUCUCCCGUGACUGAGCUUACUUUUGUGGCCAAGCAAGAAGAGGACACGGAGAAAAAAAGCCAGCGGGUUUUUCACCCUCUUUGGACCACCGUUCCUCCAGCUGGAAAGGAAGGUUUCCUCAGAGCUUCAGACACCUGCAGGCUGACCCCUCUGCUGGCACUGUCACUGUUGCCACCACUGCCGCUGUGGAAUUUCCUGGGGACCAGGGCACCAGAGAGACAGGGAGAAAGGAAAAAACCCAGGGAUCUGGCCCACUGUCUCAGAACCAGGUGACCCCUUUCCUGUUACUAGAUGCUUCUCCUGGAGCCCCCGGGCACACUCUUGCUCGCCUCUGGAUAUCGAGUUGUAUUUAGUCCAGGCUGGGGAUACCAGGGUCAGGGACAUGGCAAACUCACCGCAACCUUGGUGGCACUUCAAAUUCUGGUCUUCAACCCCCUUCUACCUGCUACUGGUCAAUUCUCAGAGGCCUCAGUAGCUCCUUUGUGUGCCUGUCUAGCCUUUUAGCCACAUUCAGUGGGCAGGGAAGGGUGGCGGGGGUGGUGCUUACCCUGUGGAGUAACCAUAAGGAAACCAGAACCAUAAGGAAAUGAGAAGAUGUGUUUUAAAGGCCUUAAACAGAAACGUCUGGGAUUACAAACAGAAAUGAGGAAGUCAGGAAUAAAGUAAAGGGUGAAUGAUUAGGUGAGAGUGAGCAGAAGCGCCUGAUAUGCAGGAUCCUGUGGGCCUCUGGAGCCCAUCCCCUAACUCCCUCACCCAUCUUUCCAUGUGCACCUUGCAGAGGGAGGAGGGAAGCCCUCUGCACCCACCCCGCCUUCCAGGUUGAGACAAAGGCUUCGACCGUCAGCACGCGAGCCUAUCCUUUCCACGGGGAGUGUCAGAAAGAUGCCGUAGGGCCAGGUGAGCUGCUGUGAAGGACUCAUUCUUGGUAGCCGGCAGUUACUGGCAACUUGUGAGCUUGGUGGGCUCCUACUAACGCACCUGGGACACCAGGCUGCUGGGCUCCCCUCUAGGCAGCCUCCCCUCCAGGCAGCCUCACCAGCAGCUCCCCUGAGCCAUGGAGACCCCAGAGGUCCCCGUGGGCUCGCUAAUCGACUUUGGGCCUGAGGCACCCACCUCUUCUCCCCUGGAGGCACCACCCCCUGUGCUGCAGGACGGCGAUGGCUCCCUGGGGGACGGUGCAUCAGAGAGUGAGACCACUGAGUCUGCGGACAGUGAGAAUGACAUGGGCGAGUCGCCCUCGCACCCGUCCUGGGACCAAGACCGCCGUUCCUCCUCCAACGAGUCCUUCUCCUCCAACCAGAGCACCGAGUCUACCCAGGAUGAAGAGACCCUGGCACUCAGGGACUUCAUGCGUGGCUACGUGGAGAAGAUCUUCUCUGGAGGGGAGGACUUGGAUCAGGAGGAGAAAGCCAAGUUUGGAGAGUACUGCAGCAGUGAAAAUGGAAAAGGCCGGGAGUGGUUUGCUCGAUACGUGAGUGCCCAGCGCUGCAACUCCAAGUGUGUCUCAGAGGCAACCUUCUACCGCCUGGUGCAGUCUUUUGCAGUGGUGCUGUUCGAGUGUCAUCAGAUGGAUGACUUUGGGCCUGCCAAGAACCUCAUGACCAUGUGCUUCACCUACUACCACAUCGGAAAACCACAGCUGCUGCCCCCGGAGUCCCGGGAGAAGCCCGCGGGCAGCAUCGACUCCUACCUGAAAUCCGCAAACAGCUGGCUGGCCGAAAAGAAGGACAUCGCCGAGCGGCUGCUGAAGAACACCUCGGCCAGGACUGAGAAUGUCAAGGGCUUCUUCGGGGGGCUGGAGACCAAGCUGAAGGGGCCCCUGGCCAGGAGGAACGAGGAAGACGAGAACAAACCCCAGGAGAAGCGGCCCAGGGCUGUGACCGCGUACAGCCCCGAGGACGAAAAGAAGGGGGAGAAGAUCUACCUGUACACGCACCUGAAGCAACAGCCCAUCUGGCACACUCUGAGGUUCUGGAAUGCAGCCUUUUUUGACGCUGUCCAUUGUGAGAGGACAAAGCGAUCUCCCACUACCAGAGGGGAUGCUGGAGAGGAGGAGGAGAAGAGGGAGAAGUGGUGCCACAUGACCCAGGAGGAGCGCGACGACAGCCUCCGGUUCAACGAGAACAUCACCUUCGGGCAGCUGGGCACAUUCACGCACAACAUGCUGGCCUUUGGACUGAACAAGAAGCUGUGCAAUGACUUCCUGAAGAAGCAGGCUGUGAUUGGCAACCUGGAUGAAGAGCAAUACAAGCUGCUUAGUGACCACAUUGAGCAAAUGGCCACUGAGUAGGCCCCAGAGGUCGCACUCCGCAGGAGGACUGAGGCCAUGUGCCAUUCUCCCGGGCCCAGCGCCCGGCCGUCACCCCACCCGAUGACCUGCAUGAAGCCAGCAGCACCCAGAGCCACUCCUGCUGCCCUAGAACUAGCGGUUAGAAGAAUCCGCUGUUCCUCCCUCAUCUCCUCUGCCUGUGUCUGCGACCCCCAUCCAUGUGCCAAAGUGUCCCUUGGGUCACACAGCUAAAGCCGAGGUGACCAGUUGUACCCCGAGUGCCAGGCUUGUGAGAUGAGACCAAGAGGGAGGAGGGGAAGGACUCCAUGGGCCAUCGUGGGCCAAGGGCUGGCGAGGGUGGGGGCGGGCAAGGGAUGCAGGCAGGACAGCCAUGAGGUGGGGCUGCAGCCGGCACACCCAGUGGUGGAGGGCCGGCGCUGCCACUCACGGUGGGUGGCCGUGGGCCACCUUCCCUGCAAUGGGUGCACACGCGGCUCCCAUCCAGCCCUCUCAGCGUGGGGCUGUGGCUGGUCCUCACUAUUCCCCAGUCUCCCGCUGUGGGGCAGGAACAGGAAGUGACGGGAACCUUGAGGAGGAAACGCCUGUGUUAGGGAGAGAGUGGGUGCGGUGUAGAGGAUGCUCUUGGCCGGCUGGAGCAAGACCUGGCUCCCACCAGAGGGACGUGUGUGUGCCUGCAGACGGCCCGGGAGCUGUGUGUCUCCGCCAGAGUCACAGCAGUGCCGAGGUGUCCGCGGCAGACCACACAGACCGUCUGAAAUGCGCCCGCCUGGCGGACAGCUCCCUUCUGAAGCAGAGAAGCCUCCAUGGUCACGAAGCAGCGUUGUGCUGUGUGUCCCUCGCAAGAAGCACAGGAAAGAGAAGUUUCUUUAGUAGCCACUAGACAACCACCCUUUCUGAAAGCAAACAGUGCUGCUCUUUAUUCCAGACAAGGCAGGAAAGUCUGAGUUGGGAGUGACAGUGGCUGGAGAGAAGCAGAUCUGUGCAACGUGCAGGGCAAGCCAGUGGCGUGGCCUCUGCCUCUAAGCGCUGAGCAUUGGGCCCCUUCCCCACCAGACCUUUGUAGCUCCUCCAGCCUCUGCAGAGACUCCCUUCACCUCGCACUUACUGCCUGGGAACCACGGCCCUUCUCUUCUGUGGGUCUGUACCAGGUACUCCAGGCCAGCCCAUGGGCCCGGGGCCUGACCCCAACACCUGCAUGCUGGGUCCAGAGCCUUCUGUUUCACCGUGCGUGGACACUGCUAGGCCGCCUGGGGUCCCCUGCCUCCUGCCUGUCGCUGCCGUGGUCCCUGACUGCGAAAUAGGCCCGCGGGGCUCUCCCUCCUCCUGCCAUCCUCCCCUCCCGCCCUUCCUGGCUACCUCCUCUGACAUGCGGUCAGAUAAGUCCCGUCUUGUUUGUGAGUACCACAGAAACGCCUGAGAGUCACUUACCCGGCCACUGCUUGGAAGGUUUCCCUCCGGGGAAUGCCUCCCUGGAAUGUUCCAGAGACGGAACAUUCUCUAGAGACAACAGUCUGUGCUGCAGAUUGGUUGGAUCACAGAAUGUGUGUCUGGGGCAUUAUCUGAAACGUGGUGUCAUCUGAUGCAUUUGGACCAUAUGCUGCCAGACUGCAGAACGGGGGAGCCGGGGCUCAGGGCCCCUGACUGCAUGGUGCAUGAGUGAUCUCAGCCUAGCGAUGCCGCUGGCCAGACCGUGACCAUGCUGCCAGUGUGCUCGCCAUGAGCUGGGUCAGGGCUGGGGAGUUGUGCAGGCUGGGGUGACCCUUCCCCCAUCAUUGGGCCCCAACGGGCAUGUCUCCACCGAAUCCAUUUAGAGAAAUGUCAGAGCGAGGGUUGUGUGGACACCCCUCGCUCUGAUGCCAACUGCAGAUAAUACACACCUCCUGCAGCGUCCAGCCACGGCUCCAGGGCACUGCUCUCCUCCUUGCACCGGUGAAACUCAGGCCACACUCAAGGGCUGACUGUCCAGGCGCUCCCUUCAGCCGCCUCGUCGUCAGCGUUCUUAGUCAUGCAUUAUUCGUGUUAGCUGAAAUGCAUUCAGACUUUGUUCUGCGGUGCCCACAGGACUUACCCCUGUAUGUACAGGAUUUUUGUAUGAAAGUUUUGUUUGAUUCUGAGACUCUCUUGGGAACGCUGGAGAGCUUGUGCACAGCCUCUGGAAGGAAAGGCAGCGCUGACUUCGUUGGGCUUUUUUCCAAGCACUUUAACUUCAGAAAUGGUCUUGACACUUUUUUCUCCACAUAGACUCUUGAAAUAGCCAUUUCAGGGGAGGAAAGGGUUGGGGUUUUCUUUGUUUGUUUGUUUGUUUCCCCCUUUACUACCUGUUCUUGUAGAUCUAGCUCCUCAGAGUUGGAGGAAGGCUGACAGAGAAGGUCUCCUCUGUGCUCCAUCCACACAGGAUGCCGGAGAGACAGCCCCUUGUGCUGUGAGCAGAGCAGGCAGUGGCUCUGGAGGCUGCCUGUGGUCUCCUUCCGGCUGUGGCUGACAGUGGCUCUGGCCAGGGUUGCUUGGAGAAGGCUCAGUGUGCCUGGGACAGGGCUUACCACCUGCCACCAAGGUUUCCUCUCUUCCCCCAGGACCUGGGCAGAGCAGGCAUGAGCUGGGCUGUGGUGCAGAGCAAGCAGACCCAGCCACACUGCUCAAAGGUCCCUGCGUGGGGAGGUGUCACACCAGGGGCACACCCAGGGCCACCUGGGUGUAGGAGAGCUCUGGUGGCCCCUCCGUAAACUCAGGAAGUGUCAGGUGAUUUCCUAGGGAGAGGUUCCCAGUCCCAGCAGGCAGAAUGCCCAAAACCAGGAGCACGAAGGCCUGUCAUCCAUGGGGCCAUUGCAGGCACUCUGCCGCCCGACCUUGAGGGCUGUGCCAAUCCUAGUGAACCAAAAUGCAAACAACUCACACAAGUGAAAAGCUCCCUGCUUUGAAAACAGGACAUGUUGACAGGCAGCAUGGUAUGUUUUUAGCCUUUGUUACAGUUUUAGCAACAUUGAUGUCUAAGAGGGGCCGUGGUAAUAGAUUGCAUCUGCCCUGUGCAUGCGCAUGUUUAACCACAGGCCAGAGAACUCAAUUCUGAUGUCGUAAGUUCUCUGUAAGUGAAAUGGGGUAGACUGUAUGAUUUUCCUAUUGCCAAAAGAAAGAAAGGGGGCCAAACAGCUCUGAAAUUUCCAAAAAAUGGCUAGAGGGAGAGUCCAGUUUCUGAGCUCUGUACCCAAAUUAAAAUCCUGAUGUUCAGGUUAAUCCAAGCAACACGCAUUGGGUUUAAAACCAGCACCGAGGCCCAGUGGGGGAAUCACAGACAUCACCAAGUCUCGUCUUCUUUCCUUCCUGUGAGUUGAAACCAAACAGGCCUCUCGCUCACUCCUCCCAGCCCAGUAAUGCUGAGGAGUUCAGUUGUGAGGAAAGAAGGCUGGAGCUGUGAGAUUCGCUUUUCCCUAGGCUGUUCCGCGUGGGUUACCUUAUCACCCUGGAGCACUUGGUAUUCCAGACCCCUGACAUGAGGAAUGCAGGUUCACACUGUAAAGAGUUUGUGAAAGGUUUCAGUCUAACUGGGGUUCCUUAGCUGGAAGCCAGGGCUGGAAGCUACAGGCCUGACCUUCCUGGGUCCCACUAUCUGUUGGCAUUUUUUUUUUUUUUUUUUUUUUAGACGGAGUUUUGCUCUUGUUGCCCAGGCUGGAGUGCAGUGACACAAUCUCUACUCACUGCAACCUCCACCUCCCGGGUUCAAGCAAUUCUCCUGCCUCAGCCUCCUGAGUAGCUGGGAUGACAGGUGCACGCCACCACGCCCGGCUAAUUUUUAUAUUUUUGGUAGAGAUGGGGUUUCACCAUGCUGGCCAGGCUGGUCUCGAACUCCUGACCUCAGGUGAUCCCCCCCACCUCAGCCUCCCAAAGUGCUGGGAUUACAGGCGUGAGGCAUCACACCUGCCUCUGUUGGCUUUUUAGUUAGGAAGGAUCCAGCUAGGCCCGUGUGGUUAGAUCAGCUUUGUUACUGAAUUACCUAAAACCAGACCACAGCACAGCCAGGGAGCCCAGUAGUGUUUCCAAGAACAGUGUGGAGCUUGAGAAAGAGAACUUUAAAAAUUAGAGGGUCCCUUUCUGCAGAGGAAGGGAUGCUCGCAGGGUGGCAGUGGCCCAGCCCCAGCCUCAGGGACGGGGAGGGAGAGCCCCCUCUGGGCCCAGCAGGCAGGUGUUCUGAGGCUGGUCCCUCCUCAGUUUCCGCAGCCACAAGGCGAAACGGCCAGAUUCUCACUCAAGGUCGUUCUCACUCCUUUUCCUGUCCCGUUUCCAGUCCCACUGAGCCAUUCACUUCUGCUGAACCAUUUUUCUUAGGAUGCAGCCGUCUCACUCCCUUGUCCUGUAAAUCGUGUAUUCAUGUUGAUGAUUCUUGGAGAUAGGUUUCACUUUUUCCCAGCUGCGUCCACAGGAAAGGGGAGUCGGAUGCCAGCUGCACCCCGCCUGGCUCGCACAGGCUAAGACCACAGACAGAGCAGGGCUUCCCGGAGCCACACAGGCCACGCACCCCAGGAACCCUUGCUGCCGCGGGCCAGGAACAGGAAUGUGUUGGUGCCUGAGACACCAAAUGGAAGAAGCACAUCAAGACUGUUCUCCUGCGGCCAACACUGGCCCGGAAGCCGCCCUCCAUACAGGCCCUCAGGGGGCCUGCCUUCUGCGCCUCAGUCCCCCGUGCAUCCCUGGGCCUGGGUAUCACAUGCUCUCCAGGAAAGGGACGGAAUCAAUCCUGUGACCGAUGGGCUCGCAAGGAUGGGUGCCGCCGUGGGAGCCCUGCCUCUGGUGCUGGCAAGGGAUUGGGUUUGUGUGGGUGUCUCUAGCCUGCAGAGUGCAGUGAGUGAGAGUCCUUGGGAGCGCGGCGCUGCCUGUAGCUGUGCCUGGGGAUGCACGUGGCCACGGGAUUUCAGUGGGACAGCGCUCCCACAGGGGCUGGGGGUGGGGGUGGGGUUUCUUAGUUACUGUUGGAAAGGGAAAAAUUCACCAUAUCCAAGGGGAGAGACGAUGGGCUGGGUUUGUUUACUCCAACUUCCCUUCUACACCCCUCCUGCAGGACAGUACGAUUUGGGGAGAACCCAGCUCCCCACUUUAUCUGCAGACUCUGGGACCUGACAAAACAGUCAGAGCCUGAGUGCACUGCAGCCUGAACUCCCUUGAGCAGCGCUAUAAGGGACUUUGCACUUUAAAAAGGGGAUGCCUGUCAGUAAAUCCCCUGUGCAUUGACUAGAACUGGGGGGCUGCGCCCGCUCCCUCCUUAAUCCUAGAUGAUUUGCUCAUGAAAUAGAGGUGGGGGACGACCGCAUGCACUCUGGGAGGUGCAGCCCUAAGGGGUGGACUCCAGAUCUCCCUGCAAGAGACAGCUUGGCUUGGCUUUGGCUGUUGGGGAGGAGUCCCUGCCAUCCCGGUGAGCCUGGGGCUGUUGCUUAGGGUCUUCUGGGUGGACACGUGGAGAAAGAGAAGGCAAACGUUGGAACACUAGGAAAAGCUAGAAAUUCAGACAACACACAUGGAUCCCCUUAAAACAUGUAAAUGUGUCAGAACACGGUUGACCUGCCGCCUUCUUGAACCUGGUGGCCCCCGUUGGAACUAUCAGUGGCGUCUCCCAUGCACACGCCCUCUGCUUUCUCUUUCCUAGACUCGCGGUGCUCACAUCCAGACAUUACCUUGUUGGUAGCCCCCAAGUGGCGUGCAGUGACACCAGUAUCUUCUCUGUUGCAUUUUUGCAAUCUUGUGUCCCGCUCGGUGAUGUUCUACAAACUCUGUUUUAAGGUUGAGAAAGUUUCAAGGGUGAAGAUCUCAAAACAGUGCUAAAAUCAAAGGUGUUUGCUGUGAAGAAAAACAUGUGUAUAUAUUGCACCUUGAGUUGUCAGAAGGUAGAAACUGAAAUAAACUAACUUUAAAAAAAAAA